CUUCGCGGCGCUUCCUAGUUCGGCUGGUUCUUCUGUCGCCGGCUUCAGCAGCCCGCGCCCGGGCAGGUAAGGCAUUCCCCGCCUUAAUGCCUCGGUCAAACGUCGUCCGAGGUCCGCUUCCAGGCCUCGGCACCUCUGCCCCAGGGUUGCUGGGGUCGGCUGCGGAACGGAAAUCUCUUUAUCAUCCGUGAGAAAAGUUAGAGAGGAAGUGGGUUCCUUUGACAGAGCUUACUCCAGAAGAAAGACUUGGGUAGGUCCCCGGUAAUCAAGAAGUUCGUCGGCCCUGAGGAAGAGCCUGAGGCUUGGAGGGACGUCACCCAGCUGUUCUGGGGCGCAGUCGGACCUCAAGUUUCUCACCUCUCAGGCCCUGGAUUCCGUGAACCCGACUGCGAAAUGAAGUCUCUUUUCCCCAGAACCAGGAAGUCAGGCCAGCACCUGACAGAUGCCUGUGGCGCCAGCAGCUCGCUGAGCCUCCACACGAUUGUAAUUCGCUUGUUUCUCCGGCCUCCAAGCUUCCAGGGAAUUAGAAAGUGGAGGCGGCUUAUGGGAUCAGAUGAGUACAUUCGCAGAUGGGGGAAAAAAGUGUACCUGUCAGCUUGGAAGCCAGAGGGAGACAAAGGGAUAAAAGCAAACCCUGUCCAGGUGCGGUGGCUCAUGCUUGUAAUCCCAGCACUUUGGGAGGCCCAGGCGGGCGGAUCGCUUGAGGUCAGGAGUUCGAGACCAGCCUGGCCAACAUGGUGAAACCCCUGUCUCUACUAAGAUACAAAAUUUAGCUGGCAUAGUGGCGGGCGCCCGUAAUGCCAGCUACUCCGGGGGCUGAGGCAGGAGAAUCGCUUGAACCCAGGAGGCAGAGGUUGCAGUGAGCCGAGAUCGUGCCACUACACUCCAGCCUGGGCAACAGAGGGAGACUCCGUCUCAAAAGAAAAAAAAAAAAAAAAAAGCAAACCCUGAGAAAGCGAGAAAGCACUUUGAGCAUUUAGAAUGGGAACAAACGGCGCUAUUAGUGCUUCAAAAACGUAACUGCCCAAGGCCCCUGGGGCCUGGAGCAGUAUCUAGCACAAAGUAGACACUCAGUAAAUAUUUGGAAUAGAAGAUGAACAAACCCAUAACACCAUCAACAUAUGUGCGCUGCCUCAAUGUUGGACUAAUUAGGAAGCUGUCAGAUUUUAUUGAUCCUCAAGAAGGAUGGAAGAAGUUAGCUGUAGCUAUUAAAAAACCAUCUGGUGAUGAUAGAUACAAUCAGUUUCACAUAAGGAGAUUUGAAGCAUUACUUCAAACUGGAAAAAGUCCCACUUCUGAAUUACUGUUUGACUGGGGCACCACAAAUUGCACAGUUGGUGAUCUUGUGGAUCUUUUGAUCCAAAAUGAAUUUUUUGCUCCUGCGAGUCUUUUGCUCCCAGAUGCUGUUCCCAAAACUGCUAAUACACUACCUUCUAAAGAAGCUAUAACAGUUCAGCAAAAACAGAUGCCUUUCUGUGACAAAGACAGGACAUUGAUGACACCUGUGCAGAAUCUUGAACAAAGCUAUAUGCCACCUGACUCCUCAAGUCCAGAAAAUAAAAGUUUAGAAGUUAGUGAUACACGUUUUCACAGUUUUUCAUUUUAUGAAUUGAAGAAUGUCACAAAUAACUUUGAUGAACGACCCAUUUCUGUUGGUGGUAAUAAAAUGGGAGAGGGAGGAUUUGGAGUUGUAUAUAAAGGCUACGUAAAUAACACAACUGUGGCAGUGAAGAAGCUUGCAGCAAUGGUUGACAUUACUACUGAAGAACUGAAACAGCAGUUUGAUCAAGAAAUAAAAGUAAUGGCAAAGUGUCAACAUGAAAACUUAGUAGAACUACUUGGUUUCUCAAGUGAUGGAGAUGACCUCUGCUUAGUAUAUGUUUACAUGCCUAAUGGUUCAUUGCUAGACAGACUCUCUUGCUUGGAUGGUACUCCACCACUUUCUUGGCACAUGAGAUGCAAGAUUGCUCAGGGUGCAGCUAAUGGCAUCAAUUUUCUACAUGAAAAUCAUCAUAUUCAUAGAGAUAUUAAAAGUGCAAAUAUCUUACUGGAUGAAGCUUUUACUGCUAAAAUAUCUGACUUUGGCCUUGCACGGGCUUCUGAGAAGUUUGCCCAGACAGUCAUGACUAGCAGAAUUGUGGGAACAACAGCUUAUAUGGCACCAGAAGCUUUGCGUGGAGAAAUAACACCCAAAUCUGAUAUUUACAGCUUUGGUGUGGUUUUACUAGAAAUAAUAACUGGACUUCCAGCUGUGGAUGAACACCGUGAACCUCAGUUAUUGCUAGAUAUUAAAGAAGAAAUUGAAGAUGAAGAAAAGACAAUUGAAGAUUAUAUUGAUAAAAAGAUGAAUGAUGCUGAUUCCACUUCAGUUGAAGCUAUGUACUCUGUUGCUAGUCAAUGUCUGCAUGAAAAGAAAAAUAAGAGACCAGACAUUAAGAAGGUUCAACAGCUGCUGCAAGAGAUGACAGCUUCUUAAAACUUUAUUGGAAAAGACUCUUGACUUUUUAUAUACACCUAUCUCAACCAUUUUUUUAACUGAUUUUUUUCCUAAAUAUUCUUCUUUACCUUUAACAAGGCAUAGGCUGUUGCAGGACAGUGGUUAUUAAAGCAUGGGUUGAACUUCCAAAAUAUAAAAAUAGAGCCACCAUAUCAACACUUAGCCCUACCCAUUAGUAUCACCCCCAGUUCUUACAGUAAUCCCUGAGAAAUCUCCUUCAAGCAUCACCAAACACAGUUUGAAAAUUACAGGGUUAGCAAAAAGAGCCUGGGCUGUAUGUAGGGUGGAAACACUCUGAUCUGAAGCCCAGCUGACUCCACUACUAAUUUGCUGUAAAGCUUUGGACAUACACUUAGCUGCUGUGAGCCACUAAUAACAUUGGGCUAAUAUCUGCUGUGCUUCUCUGACAGGUAGUCAUGAAAAUCAAAUGAUGCAAAAUAUAUACAAGCACUUUGUAAAUUGUAAAAUGAUACAAAAUUUAAAGUUUAUAGAGCCAGUUACAAAAUCCUAUUAGUCAUAUAUUUAUAGAUUGUGUUCACAGCAAUCAUUUAACCACAAAUAAAAUAUCCCUUGAUGAUACUGCCAUAAUGAUAUGUCCAUUAUUAGAUUAUGUUACAUGACAAAGUUGAAGGAAUUUGGCAGAUGCAGUUAAGGUUCCUAAACAACUCACUUUGAGACUGUUGAAAGGGCCUGACCUAAUCAAGUGAACCCUUGCAAGAAGAAUUCUCCUUGUAAGCCUUGAAGAAGUAUGUGAGAGGGCCACAUUGGCUAAAACCUAAAGGUGGCCUCUAGGAGAUGAGACCUACCUUCCAGUUGUCAGCAAGCAGGAAAAAAAAAUUGGGACCUCAGUUGCAACCACAAGGAACUGAAUUCUGCCAAAAAUCUGAGUCAGCUUAGAAGAGUACUCCAAGCUUCAGAUGAUAACCACAGCCUGGGCUGACACCUGGAUUUCAGCUUUGCAUGAUCCUCAGUAUGAGAAUCUAUCUGUUCUGUGCUGGACUUCUAAUAUAUAGAACUGUGAGAUAAUGGGUCACAUUGGCUGGAUGUGGUGGCUCAUACCUGUAAAUCCCAGCACUUUGGGAGGCCGAGGCAGGCAGAUCACCUGAGGUCAAGAGUUCAAGACCGGCCUGGCCAACAUGGUGAAACCCCGUCUCUACUAAAAAUACAAAAAUUAGACGAGCGUGGUGGUGGACACCUGUAGUCCCAGCUACUUGGGAGGCUGAGGCAGGAGACUAGCUGGAACCAGGGAGGUAGAGGUUGCAGUGAGCUGAGAUCGUGCCACUGCACUCCAGCCUGGGUGACAGAGUGAGACUCCAUCAUAAAUAAAUAAAUAAAUAAAUGGGUCACAUUAAGCCUUUAAGUUUGUGGUAAUUUAUUAUUCAGUAAUAGAAAACAAAUACAGAUACUCUCCCAUGAUGUUUUUCCCAUGAUGAUUUCCCAUGAUAUUUACAGGUUUUGCCCACAUUUGAGGGGUAUGUGGAAAUUAUACAGAGCAUGUACAGCGGGAGGCUUAUAGUGUACGUACUGAAAUGUGGGGUUGGAGCCCCAACACAGAGACCCCAGCAGGACACUGCCUAGUAGAGCUAUGGGAAGGGUGCUGCCACCCUCCAGACUUGAGAAUUGUAGAGCCACCAGCAGCUUGCACUCUGAGCUUGGAAAAGCCACAGGCACUCAACUUCAACCAUGAGGGAAGCCACGCACCCUGCAAAGCCACAGGAGUGGAGCUGCCCACGGCCUCGAGGGCCCACCCCUUGCACCAGUGUGCCAGGAUGUGGGACAUGGAAUCAAGGAAUAUGUUAGGGCUUUUUUUUUUUUUUUUUUGAGACGGAGUCUUGCUCUGUUGCCCAGGCUGGAGUGCAGUGGCACGAUCUCGGCUCACUGCAAGCUCUGCCUCCCAGGUUCACGCCAUUCCCCUGCCUCAGCCUCCCCAGUAGCUGGGACUACAGGUGCCCGCCACCAUGCCCAGCUAAUUUUUUUUGUAUUUUUAGUAGAGAUGGGGUUUCACUGUGUUAGCCAGGAUGGUCUUGAUCUCCUGACCUCGUGAUCACCCGCCUCGGCCUCCCAAAGUGCCAGUAUUUAAAGUUUAAUGUCUUCCCAGCUGGGUUUCAGACUUGCCAGGAUCCUGUUGCCCCUUUCUUUAGCCAAUUUCUCCCUUUUGGGACAAGAAUGUUUUACUUAUUGCCUGUACCACCAACUGUAUCUUGGAAAUAAAUAACUUAUAUUUUAUUUCAGAGGCUCAUAGGCGGCAGGAACUUACCUUGAGUCUCAAAUGAGACUUAGGACUUUUGAGUGAUGCUAGAAUGAGUUAAGACUUUGGGAAGGGAUGAUUAUAUUUUGCAAUGUGAGAAAGACAUUAGAUUUGGGGGGCUGGGGGUAGAAUGACAUUGUUUAGAUGUUUGUCUCCUUCAAAUUUCAUGUUUAAAUGUAAUCCCCAGUGUUGGGGGUGGAGGUGGGGCCUGAUGGGAAGUGUUUGGGUCAUGGUGGAUGAUCCCUCAUGAAUGGCUUAGAGCCACUGGUGAUGAGUGAGUUCUCACUCAGUUCGUGUGAGAUCUGGUGGCUUAAAAGAGUCUGCUCCCCCUUUGCCUUCCAUUGUGAUUGUAACCUUCCUGGGGCCUUCAUCAAAGGCCAGGCAAAUAUUGGUGCCGUGCUAGUAUGGCCUGCAGAACCGUAAGCCAAAACAAACCUUUUUUCUUUAUAAAUUACCCAGCCUCAGUUAUUCCUUUAUAGUGAUGCAAAACGGGCUAACUAUAUAAAUUUGUAAUUUUUAAGUUAUAGAUUGUUUUUAUUAAACACUUAUGAAUACUG